CUGCACUGGCUCGGGAUGGGGACCAGAGGCUGCUAAUCCAUCAUCAUUAACGAAUAGAGUGGGUGACAGUCCCUGAUAACUGGGAACAGGUUGCAGAGCUUAGCCACAGGAUCACGCUCCAGGCUGUUGGCCAGCAGGACCAGGCUCGAUGCUGAGUCAAAGAUCAACUUAGGAGGAAAUUUGAGUUUUGGGUGAGAGCGACUCCCUGGUGGCCUCAGCCCUGUGACACUCACAUCCAGGACAGUUCCCGGUGCCAAGCGCUGGUUAUGUGUGGGGGGCUUGACUCCCUGGUCCCAACGAGGUCUCAGUGUGUUGCCCAGGCUGGUCUUGAACUCCUGAGUUCAAGCAAUCGUCUCAGCCCAGCCUCCCAAAGUGGUAGGAUUACAGGCGAGAGCCACUGCGCCCGGCCCCUGGUCCCAGUUCUCACCACAGCCCCUGCAGUAAGCAGUCGGGUAUGUCACUGACAGAGCAGAAGCUCAGGGGACUAAAACUCCCCGCCUGAGUUCCCUGGUGAAUGGAUGGUGGGGCCGAGUUCCAUUCCAGGCUGGAUGGAGCCCAGAGCUGUGGGUCUCCUACCCUCCCAUCCCCUCAUUCCAGCUUGAUCUUCCUUAAGAGACUCAUACGCCCCAACCCCUUGGUCUGAGUAUCUUAGAUUGUUCUCGUGGUUCCUCCGUCCUUCACCACUGAAGGCUGCUGUUCAUUCUCUCUCCGUCUCUGUCCCUUAUUGCUCUCACGUCUGUCUCUGUCAUCUUUUCACUCCUUGUCCCUCUUACUCCGUUCUUUGGCCCCCAAUGAAAGCUGAGUCAGAGACAGACGCUUCCCCUCAGUUCCCAGUGCCUCCCUUGGGGGCCCCUCCUUGGCUGUAUCCGUCAGUGGCUCCAGGCUGCCGCGCGCAGGCUUAGCUCAUUCCUCUGACCUGCCAGGAAGCAGAGAGACCCACAGAGCAGGAGGGAGGCAGAAAGUGGAGACGGACCUGAGCCCGAGGAAGAGGCAGGCAGAGGCUGAGGCUGAUUCCACCCCAGCCUGCCUGGACAACCCUCCUUAGCCGCAGCCCCUUCCAGUUCCCUAGGGGUUCUGCCCCUCCCCCUCUCUGGGGCACCAGCCCCCCAGGGUCCUGCAUCCCACCAUGUCGAUGGCUGUGGAAACCUUUGGCUUCUUCAUGGCAACUGUGGGGCUGCUGAUGCUGGGGGUGACUCUGCCAAACAGCUACUGGCGAGUGUCCACUGUGCACGGGAACGUCAUCACCACCAACACCAUCUUCGAGAACCUCUGGUUUAGCUGUGCCACCGACUCCCUGGGCGUCUACAACUGCUGGGAGUUCCCGUCCAUGCUGGCCCUCUCUGGGUAUAUUCAGGCCUGCCGGGCACUCAUGAUCACCGCCAUCCUCCUGGGCUUCCUCGGCCUCUUGCUAGGCAUAGCGGGCCUGCGCUGCACCAACAUUGGGGGCCUGGAGCUCUCCAGGAAAGCCAAGCUGGCGGCCACCGCAGGGGCCCUCCACAUUCUGGCCGGUAUCUGCGGGAUGGUGGCCAUCUCCUGGUACGCCUUCAACAUCACCCGGGACUUCUUCGACCCCUUGUACCCCGGAACCAAGUACGAGCUGGGCCCCGCCCUCUACCUGGGGUGGAGCGCCUCACUGAUCUCCAUCCUGGGUGGCCUCUGCCUCUGCUCCGCCUGCUGCUGCGGCUCUGACGAGGACCCAGCCGCCAGCGCCCGGCGGCCCUACCAGGCUCCAGUGUCCGUGAUGCCCGUCGCCACCUCGGACCAAGAAGGCGACAGCAGCUUUGGCAAAUACGGCAGAAACGCCUACGUGUAGCAGCUCUGGCCCGUGGGCCCCGCUGUCUUCCCACUGCCCCAAGGAGAGGGGACCUGGCCGGGGCCCAUUCCCCUAUAGUAACCUCAGGGGCCGGCCACGCCCCGCUCCCGUAGCCCCGCCCCGGCCACGGCCCCGUGUCUUGCACUCUCAUGGCCCCUCCAGGCCAAGAACUGCUCUUGGGAAGUCGCAUAUCUCCCCUCUGAGGCUGGAUCCCUCAUCUUCUGACCCUGGGUUCUGGGCUGUGAAGGGGACGGUGUCCCCGCACGUUUGUAUUGUGUAUAAAUACAUUCAUUAAUAAAUGCAUAUUGUGACCGUU